ACCCGCCCCGGCUACUCCAACCCCUGGGCGGGCGGGGGUACCGCCUGGGCAAGGGCCGGGGCGCCGGGCCGAGCCACCUCUUCCCCUCCCCCGCUUCCCUGUCGCGCUCCGCUGGCUGGACGCGCUGGAGGAGUGGAGCAGCACCCGGCCGGCCCUGGGGGCUGACAGUCGGCAAAGUUUGGCCCGAAGAGGAAGUGGUCUCAAACCCCGGCAGGUGGCGACCAGGCCAGACCAGGGGCGCUCGCUGCCUGCGGGCGGGCUGUAGGCGAGGGCGCGCCCCAGUGCCGAGACCCGGGGCUUCAGGAGCCGGCCCCGGGAGAGAAGAGUGCGGCGGCGGACGGAGAAAACAACUCCAAAGUUGGCGAAAGGCACCGCCCCUACUCCCGGGCUGCCGCCGCCUCCCCGCCCCCAGCCCUGGCAUCCAGAGUACGGGUCGAGCCCGGGCCAUGGAGCCCCCCUGGGGAGGCGGCACCAGGGAGCCUGGGCGCCCGGGGCUCCGCCGCGACCCCAUCGGGUAGACCACAGAAGCUCCGGGACCCUUCCGGCACCUCUGGACAGCCCAGGAUGCUGUUGGCCACCCUCCUCCUCCUCCUCCUUGGAGGCGCUCUGGCCCAUCCAGACCGGAUUAUUUUUCCAAAUCAUGCUUGUGAGGACCCCCCAGCAGUGCUCUUAGAAGUGCAGGGCACCUUACAGAGGCCCCUGGUCCGGGACAGCCGCACCUCCCCUGCCAACUGCACCUGGCUCAUCCUGGGCAGCAAGGAACAGACUGUCACCAUCAGGUUCCAGAAGCUACACCUGGCCUGUGGCUCAGAGCGCUUAACCCUACGCUCCCCUCUCCAGCCACUGAUCUCCCUGUGUGAGGCACCUCCCAGCCCUCUGCAGCUGCCCGGGGGCAACGUCACCAUCACUUACAGCUAUGCUGGGGCCAGAGCACCCAUGGGCCAGGGCUUCCUGCUCUCCUACAGCCAAGCCCCUCUCCAUGGUGCCUCUGCAGAUUGGCUGAUGUGCCUGCAGGAAGAGUUUCAGUGCCUGAACCACCGCUGUGUAUCUGCUGUCCAGCGCUGUGAUGGGGUUGAUGCCUGUGGCGAUGGCUCUGAUGAAGCAGGUUGCAGCUCAGACCCCUUCCCUGGCCUGACCCCAAGACCCGUCCCCUCCCUGCCUUGCAAUGUCACCUUGGAGGACUUCUAUGGGGUCUUCUCCUCUCCUGGAUAUACACACCUAGCCUCAGUCUCCCACCCCCAGUCCUGCCAUUGGCUGCUGGACCCCCAUGAUGGCCGGCGGCUGGCCGUGCGCUUCACAGCCCUGGACUUGGGCUUUGGAGAUGCAGUGCAUGUGUAUGACGGCCCUGGGCCCCCUGAGAGCUCCCGACUACUGCGUAGUCUCACCCACUUCAGCAAUGGCAAGGCUGUCACUGUGGAGACACUGUCUGGCCAGGCUGUUGUGUCCUACCACACAGUUGCUUGGAGCAAUGGUCGUGGCUUCAAUGCCACCUACCAUGUGCGGGGCUAUUGCUUGCCUUGGGACAGACCCUGUGGCUUAGGCUCUGGCCUGGGAGCUGGCGAAGGCCUAGGUGAGCGCUGCUACAGUGAGGCACAGCGCUGUGACGGCUCAUGGGACUGUGCUGACGGCACAGAUGAGGAGGACUGCCCAGGCUGCCCACCUGGACACUUCCCCUGUGGGGCUGCUGGCACCUCUGGUGCCACAGCCUGCUACCUGCCUGCUGACCGCUGCAACUACCAGACUUUCUGUGCUGAUGGAGCAGAUGAGAGACGCUGUCGGCAUUGCCAGCCUGGCAAUUUCCGAUGCCGGGACGAGAAGUGCGUGUAUGAGACGUGGGUGUGCGAUGGGCAGCCAGACUGUGCGGACGGCAGUGAUGAGUGGGACUGCUCCUAUGUUCUGCCCCGCAAGGUCAUUACAGCUGCAGUCAUUGGCAGCCUAGUGUGCGGCCUGCUCCUGGUCAUCGCCCUGGGCUGCACCUGCAAGCUCUAUGCCAUUCGCACCCAGGAGUACAGCAUCUUUGCCCCCCUCUCCCGGAUGGAGGCUGAGAUUGUGCAGCAGCAGGCACCCCCUUCCUACGGGCAGCUCAUUGCCCAGGGUGCCAUCCCACCUGUAGAAGACUUUCCUACAGAGAAUCCUAAUGAUAACUCAGUGCUGGGCAACCUGCGUUCUCUGCUACAGAUCUUACGCCAGGAUAUGACUCCAGGAGGUGGCCCAGGUGCCCGCCGUCGUCAGCGGGGCCGCUUGAUGCGACGCCUGGUACGCCGUCUCCGCCGCUGGGGCUUGCUCCCUCGAACCAACACCCCGGCUCGGGCCUCUGAGGCCAGAUCCCAGGUCACACCUUCUGCUGCUCCCCUUGAGGCCCUAGAUGGUGGCACAGGUCCAGCCCGUGAGGGCGGGGCAGUGGGUGGGCAAGAUGGGGAGCAGGCACCCCCACUGCCCAUCAAGGCUCCCCUCCCAUCUGCUAGCACGUCUCCAGCCCCCACUACUGUCCCUGAAGCCCCAGGGCCACUGCCCUCACUGCCCCUAGAGCCAUCACUAUUGUCUGGAGUGGUGCAGGCCCUGCGAGGCCGCCUGUUGCCCAGCCUGGGGCCCCCAGGACCAACCCGGAGCCCCCCUGGACCCCACACAGCAGUCCUGGCCCUGGAAGAUGAGGACGAUGUGCUACUGGUGCCACUGGCUGAGCCGGGGGUGUGGGUAGCUGAGGCAGAGGAUGAGCCACUGCUUACCUGAGGGGACCUGGGGGCUCUACUGAGGCCUCUCCCCUGGGGGCUCUACUCAUAGUGGCACAACCUUUUAGAGGUGGGUCAGCCUCCCCUCCACCACUUCCUUCCCUGUCCCUGGAUUUCAGGGACUUGGUGGGCCUCCCGUUGACCCUAUGUAGCUGCUAUAAAGUUAAGUGUCCCUCAGGCAGGGAGAGGGCUCACAGAGUCUCCUCUGUACGUGGCCAUGGCCAGACACCCCAGUCCCUUCACCACCACCUGCUCCCCACGCCACCACCAUUUGGGUGGCUGUUUUUAAAAAGUAAAGUUCUUAGAGGAUCAUAGGUCUGGACACUCCAUCCUUGCCAAACCUCUACCCAAAAGUGGCCUUAAGCACCGGAAUGCCAAUUAACUAGAGACCCUCCAGCCCCCAAGGGGAGGAUUUGGGCAGAACCUGAGGUUUUGCCAUCCACAAUCCCUCCUACAGGGCCUGGCUCACAAAAAGAGUGCAACAAAUGCUUCUAUUCCAUAGCUACGGCAUUGCUCAGUAAGUUGAGGUCAAAAAUAAAGGAAUCAUACAUCUCAAAAUUUUGCAAAUUAGCUGCGAGCCUGAGCCCCGCCUCUGCCCAUCUCAGUCUAUGCUCACCUCAUCCCACUCCUCCCUGUGGAGCCCUUUGCUUGGCCCUCUACCUCCUGCCCUCUUCCUGUUCAUCUCCCAACCACUGCACUCUUGAUUUUUAUACCACACAGAAGGUAAGAAAAUUCUAGGAACCCUAAGGAUCAAUCCUCUCCAUUUUCACUCAAAUGCCUGGGGCCCAGCUCUGCAAUGACUGACUCCAGGGCCUCUUUCCUCACUGCCAGCAUAGAAGUCAGGGGAGCCAGCUGGGCCCUGCGGUCAGGAAGGUUCUCAUUUUUGGAGCAUACCCUGAGCCCAGAUCAUAGGAGCAGCUGUCCCUGGUGGGACACAGGAGUCAUGACUCCUACCCUCCACCCUCCACACCCACCAGGCAUUUAGCAGUCUGUCCUAUGCAAGACAGAUGAAUUCUCAGCCAGGAUACCUCAAGGCAGGCAAAGGUGAGUGGAGGGAGAAUUCACAAACAUUCAGGGUGUGUGGUGCUGGCAUCACCAUGGCCAAAUCCAAGAGGUCUUCCUGGAAGAGGGCCCAAACUGGAACCAAAAGAAUGCUGUCAGCAGUUGGAAUAGAGCUGUGAAUUCUAGACAGGGGGAGUGUCCCCAGAACAAGCAAACGGAGGAGACAAGAGGGCAAGGGUUAUAGGAAAGACCCUGGGCCUGAGAGCACAAGCAGCGGCCAGAGCUGCAGCGCUGGGGUGGGUGAUGGAGGGAAUGAUUCGCAAGCAGUGUUGGAACCCAGCCCCUAGUGAGCAAAGUGACAGAAGCUGCCCCAGAGUUUGGAAGGAAGAUCGAGGCAGAAGAUGUAGAAGGAAGCUGUGGGGGUGGGAGUGAUGCCUCAGGAACAAAACUGAGGAAUUCCCUAACGGACCCAGUCCCUGGGGAAAGAGGCUCCCCUCAGGCUCUCCUUGUCUAGCCCCACACCUGGCAGAGCCUGUCACCCAGCCUAGCCCCACGCCUGGCAGAGCCCAUCACCCAGCCUAGCCCCACACCUGGUGGAGAGGCCCUGUUGAUUACACCCUGUCAGCCUCCUCAAACCCAGCACUAAUUGCACAAUUUUCCUCUCUUCUAGUGAGCAAGAGCCUGAGGAAGUAGCAGAGAGGGGUGUGGGCCCAUGUGCAGUUCUGGGACCCUGGCACCUUGGCUCAGGGAAGACCCGAGCUCCUUUCACUGCAGACCCUCUCCAGAGACUGGGGAGAGGGCUCUGGAGAACCUGGUUCUUGCUUACUGUUCUCCCUUUGGGCCCUCCUUCCCAAACGCAAACAAUCCAGGAUCCACUCAGCGUCAGGCCCAAUGGAAAUAGUGAAGCAGUGAUUUUCCCUCCCCUGCCUCUCCAUAGCCUGGUCUUUUGCCCUCUCCUUUGCUCUUCUCUUCCCCCAUAGCCACCUCAAAUACCUGCAGCCUGAUAUCUUCAUCCCUUCAUCCAGACCUUUUCUCUCCUAGUGGUAUUGCAAACUGAAAGUGGACAAAGACUUAAGGUAAACCUGCUCCUCAUGGUGGAAUGCUUCCAAAUGCUGGAAGGAGGACUUUAGGGCAGAGUUCACUAAGGAGGCUUGUGCUUAUAGAUCAGUGGGCCUGAAAGAAGUUUCUCUAGGUUCUGGUUGUGUGCUGUACGAGGUGUAGGUAGUAAUAAUACUCUUGUCAGCCACAGUGAAGCCCCAAGCUAGCCGGGAUAGGGGACUGACCUUGUACAGGCAGCAUGGAGAAACUAAGACAGAGUGUCCUGCCCAAGUGAUGGCACUGGGGAGCAGUCACUCAGGUUUAUUUCCACCAGGGCCCAAGAAAAAAAGAAAUGAGGCAACCUAAAAUUCCAUCAAGAUAGAUACCAAUAUCCAAGGUGCUUGGUCUUAGCGGUGUGGGACCCACGUUAAGGCUCUUGGUGGGAAGGUGGGAGGUGUUUUCAGCAUGAGAUAGGGUUCAGGCUGUGAAUCAGAGUCUAGAGCCUAAGAUAAAAGAAGAUACCAGGGCUGGGCCACGGUGGCUUUCGCCUGUAAUCCUAGCACUUUGGGAGGCCAAGGCAGGCAGACUGCCUGAGCUCAGGAGUUCGAGACUAGCCUGAGCAACACGGUGAAACCCUGUCUCUACUAAAAUACAAAAAAGUAGCCAGGUGUGGCGGCAUGCACCUGUAGUCCCAGCUACUCGAGAGGCUGAGGCAGGAGAAUUGCUUGAACCCGGGAGGCGGAGGUUGCAGUGAGUGGAGAUCGCGCCACUGCACUCUAGCCUGGGUGACAGAGCGAGACUCCUUCUCCAAAAAAAAAGAAAAGAAGAUACCAGAACUCAGUCCUUAAGAAACAAAAUUCUGCCAGGCGCAGUAGCUCACACCUGUAAUCCCAGCACUUUGGAGGGGCCAAGGCAGGCGGAUCGCUUGAGGCCAAGAGUUCAAGAACAGCCUGGGCAACAUGAUGAAACCCUGUCUCUACCAAAAAUACUAAAAAUUAGCCAGUCUCACAACCUGGUCUCAAAAUAAAUAAAUAGAUUUAAAAAAAAAAUCAUGGGCCUGAACCAAGCUCCAGACCUCACUAGGAGGGGAGAAGGACCCCCCAGCCACACAGCCCAAGGCUGCAGAAGCACCUAGGUGGUUAGAGAGUGAGUGCCUGGAUGGGGCGCAGUGGCUCACACCUGUAAUCCCAGCACUUUGGGAGGCCGAGGCAGGCGGAUCACGAGGUCAAGAGAUCAAGACCAUCCUGGCCAACAUGGUGACACCGUGUCUCUACUAAAAAUACAAAAAUAAGCUGGGCAUGGUGGUGCGUGCCUGUAGUCCCAUCUACUCGGGAGGCUGAAGCAGGAGAAUCACUUGAACCUGGGAGGCAAAGGUUGCAGUGAGCUGAGAUCGCGCCACUGCACUCCAGCCUGGCAACAGAGCGAGACAAGACUCCAUCUCAAAAAAAAAAGUGAGUGCCCGAUGAUGCCAGAUUCUUCAUCACCUGAAGUGAACCCACACAACAGGGCUGGGCCAUGGGCAUCAUAAACCCCAUUUUGCAAGCUCAGGAGGAGCUUUAGGGAAAUCAGAAGACUGGCCCAGUCUCUACCAAGUGGUGGAUUUAGAGCCGGCAUGGCUUCGUUCCAAAUCUCACCCUUGUCCCACCAUUCCAUGGGACCUCCCAUUCCUGAGGGAGCCUGGAUACGGGCAAGUGCACAACCCGGGAGGUUGAGGUUACAGUGAGCCAUGAUCGCACCACUGCAGUCCAGCCCGAGCAAUAGGGUGAGACCCUCCCUCUGAAAAAAAUAAAAAUACUCAUUUUGGAAGGAAGUCAUUCUAAAAUGUUACACUUGUCUUCAGCAUAUCUGCAAUAUAAUAAUUUUCUGCAUAACUGAGGAUCAUUCACAGAAACCAAUGGCUUUUCUCCAGCAGUGUCUUCUGAAGUUGUAACAGUAGGGGCACGGGGAGCUAUUUGCUUUUAUGCUAAAUGACCUUAGACCACUUAUAAAAUGCAUAUGAGUGCUUUAAAUGUUAUUUUGUGUGUGUGUGGUGUUGCCUCCCUGACUACAAGGGGUCACUUGCUACUCUAAAUGUGUUUCUAAUCUACUAGUACAGGAACACACAUGGACACGUUAAAAUUGUGAAUAAAAGUAAGUAAAAAGUAAAA